GAGAGCAGGUUAUAAAAUGUGUCUUAUCAGACUUAAAAGAGUGCCUGGCUCUUAGUUGAUUAUCUCCUGGAUCUGGAAAGGGGAAAGGAGAUUCUCUAUAGAAUGCGGAUUUUUCCCACAAGAAACUUUGUAGGGCAAUUUCAAGAUAUGGCAGAGAGACAUGUUUUGGGGUAAAACAUUUUGAUUUUCUUCCUCCUUAUGCCAGAGUCACAUGGGAAAGUAAGUCAUAAUAUACAGGGUUAAAUAAAACCCAUCUGAUGAGAAUUUGUGGUUUGUAGGGCAGGACUCCCCAGACCCUUUAGAUAUGAAUUUGGGCAAGAUAAAAAAAAAAAUCAGAGAUUAGUCCUCAUUCAUAUGUUUUAUGAAAUUGUUUAUCAUAAGGACUUUAGAGUCAGAGAAAAAGAUCAUUAGGAGUUAGUCUAACUAAAGUUUAAUGAUGAAAAGACUGAGGCUUGCAAUUAAAGUAUUUAAUAAUAAACUAAUACAGCAACUAAGAUAGCAACUGUUUCCUGAUGUCCAAAAGUGACUCAGAAUAUGAUAAAGUAUGGAAUUAUAUUGAAAUGUUAUCUUUUACCUAACCAGUAGUUUGUAACAUUAAAGUUCACAUGAAACUGUUCUAUAUUUUUAUAAAAUUGGAAGUUGGUUAAGCAUGGCUCUAGAAUUAACAGAUGUGUGUACGCACACACACACAACCAAAUCACACAAAACUAUUCUGGCUUCCCUCUGUUUUUGUUACUUAUCGAUUCUAUAGGCAGGAUCAAAGUCAGGGUUAUCUUGUCUGCUAAAAAGCAGACAAGGAAAAAAAGGAAAAAAAAGAUUGGGUAACUGUCCUCUGGUAACUUUGCAUCAGUAAUUAUGAGAUAUUUUCACUUAGUACUUUCGCAUCUGAUGUCCAUCUUACUGACGAGACUUAAACCAUUACCUACCUCAGGUUUCCCAGAUAUUUCCCACAUAUUCCCCCUGCCAAUUUUGUUAUACUGUUACAAAACCCUCCGGAGUAAGUAUUUUCCGAAAGAACCAUUUUCUAAUUUUCUAACAUUACAAAAGAGCAAGGAUAAAAGAACCCCAAACUGAUGUUUUGGAAAGCAUUCUACUUUGAAAGUAACUUCUGGUUCAGAGGAUGAAUUUUAAAAUGUGGUAAUGUUUCUGGUGUGCCUGGGAAGAUGCAAUAAAGUUUGUUAGGUACGCAGGCAAAUUUCAGUCAUUUGUAUGUCAGGAUAAUCACAACUUACAGAAAAGGAGCAAGAAGAUAAUGAAUGAGGAACCCUGGGACUGAAAACAUUUGGAGGGAGCACAAGUACUAAGACAGAUGUUUUGAAUUUUUAUACUCAAUAGUCCAUUCUUUUGUGCAGGAUACAGUUCAUUCAUUUAACCAAUGUAUAUUGAGCAUUUUCUAUGUGCCAAUUACUAUUCUAGAUGCCAGGGAUACAUGAGUAAACACAACCGAGUUUAGAGCAGAGUCAUAUGAUCCAGCUUAAGUUCUUAAAAGAAUCAUUGCUGUGUGGAAGAUAGUGGAAGAGUGGAAACAGGGAAACCCGUUAAAAAGGCUUUUGACAUAAUCUGAACAAGAGAUGAUGAUGGCUUGGCCAACAGUAGUAGUACUGUUGGAGAUAAUGAGAAGUGGUUCAAUUCAGAUUAUAUUUUGAAGGUGCAGCCAAUAGAAAUUUUUAAUAAAUUGGUUUAUAGAGUAUGAUAGAAAACAAAGUUUAAGGCUUGAAAUAAGGAAAAUUGCAGAGGAGAAAGUUGGGGAAUAAGGAGUGGAAAGUAGAAUUCAGUUUUGUUUGUAAGUUUGAGAUGCGCAUUAGCCAUCUAGGUGGAGAUGUCUCAAGUUAAUGGGAAAGGCCAGGCGAGAGAUAAGUGAGAGUUGUCAGCACAUGAAUAGUUUUUCUUUCCUAAAACAAUUCUUUCUUCAUACAAUCUACAGGAAGUGGGAGUAGUAGUUCAAUGUUAGAUGAAAUCACAAAAUGGAUGAAUGUAGAAAAAAGGUGAGAAACUGAAAUUUUAGAGGUUUAAGAGGAUAAGGAUCCAGGAAAGGAAAGUAAAAGGAGCAGCCACUAAAAUAGGAGAACCACCGAAGGAGUACUAUGGAAGCCACUUUAAGACCAUGCUUCAAACUAUCAUAUUCUUUCUUACAUGUAUGGUUUACCUCCAAAUUAAAAAGUAAAAGUAUAUGGUGAGGGACGGAUUAACUAUGUUAAAUGCUGCUAAUAGAUGGAGAAGGUGAAAAUUGAGAUUGACAGUUUAUUUAGCAACCUGGAAGCUAUUGGUGAUUCUAAACAAGAGCAGUAAAAGCCUGCCCAAAAUGGGAUCAAAAAAAGAUUAGGAGGAGGAGAAGGAGAGACAAGUAUAAAGAAAUCUAUAGGAUGGUAACGGUAAUCAAAGGAGUUUGUUCGUUUGUUUUUAAUUUGGGAAUGUGUUAAUAGAUGGAAUGAUCCAGUAAAGGGGGAAAUUGUACUGAAUAACAUGCAUACAAGAAUCUAUGUCUACUUUAGGAUCUAUUUAAUGUGAAUUCAUGGCUUUUUUUUUUUUUUUGAUAUGAAGUCUCACUCUGUCGCCCAGGCUGGAGUGCAGUGGAGCGAUCUUGGCUCACUGCAAGCUCCACCUUCUGGGUUCACGCCAUUCUCCUGCCUCAACCUCCUGAGUAGCUGGGACUACAGGCGCCCGCCACCACGCCCGCCUUAUUUUUUGUAUUUUUAGUAGAGACAGGGUUUCACGGCUUUAGCCAAGAUGGUCUGGAUCUCCUGACCUCAUGAUCCGCCCGCCUCGGCCUCCCAAAGUACUGGGAUUACAGGCGUGAGCCACUGCGCCUGGCCUCAUGGCUCUUUUUGGACAGGGUCAUAAGCUUCUUAGAUCUGUCACCCAAUGUAAUUAAUUGAUGUAUUGGUUAAUACUGUCUUUAGCAGUGCUAGGGGAUUGGUAAGAAAUCCACAUCAUCUCUGCGCUUGGGAAAUUUACAAUCUAGAGUUGGCUAAGUGGAGAAAACAUAAGAGAGCACAUACAACUAACAAAUUCAGAUUAUGGACAAUGUACUUAAAAAACCCCCACGCCCUAGCUAUUGGCACGUGGUAAUUUUGCCCAGAGUUUUGGUUAUAUGCAUAAUCCAGAGGGGUGUAGAAAACCAGGUCCUUUCAGUACCAAUCUAAGGAAGACAUGAAUUGGGGUGUUUAUAAACCUUGGUGAGGAAGAGAAUUUUAACUGGGACUGGUAACUUGGUGGGCCCAUUGACAUACAGUAGAUUGUGAAGAAGAAAACCCCAAGGAUUAUAAGGAAUAGUUUUAAUAUUACUAAUUUUUAUCCUUUGCUGAAACUAUGGGUUUCUUAUUUGAAAUGGCAAUCAAAUAAUUUGUAAGAGUUUGUAGAAAGUGGAAAGAUUAUUGUAAUACAGGGUAGAUAUUUGCAUUUGUACAUACUUGAGGGUAAGUACAAGAAAUAAACACUUGUAAUGGGGAUUACUUAAGCAAAAUGGAUGACACCGACAGCCUUUCUGUACAACAAAUAAUUGCUGUGCUUCUCUACUCCAGUAAUGAAUGUAGUGCCCUGCUGGAUCUGGGACAGCAAGACUUUUGAGUCCAGAUUCGCCAUCCCAUUUCUUGUUCCCUAACGUUUCCUCAGAAGCGAGCGAGCCUCUUCCACAAUUUGGGGACACUGUGGAAGAACUUCUUGCUUGGGGAGUUCUGCAGCAGUCGAAGGUACAAGAAUAUAAAAACUGGUAUCUCGACACAGCUCUUACAGCAUAUUCUCAACACAAGGAACAGUAAUGUGCCGCAGCAAUUCCUUCGGUGGAAAAAACUGACUGUAUCCGCCCUUAGCUCCAGGGACCAGCCUACUGAACAUCGAAAAGGUCAGGAACGAGAUCACGGGACUGAGACGGCGAGCCGGCUAGAGCGGAUAGAGCCGUACUGCCGCUCUAGUUUUUCUUUUGCUCUCUAUGGUUAGGAGCGCAAGCCUCUCUUCGGCCCGGAAAGAUUUAAGUUCGUGAAUGCAUACGCAAGACUCGGAGGUAGUUCCGGUUCCGGCGUGGCCAUUUUCGUUGGUGGUGUUCAGUUGUGGCGGUUGCUGGUCAGUAACAGCCAAGAUGCUGCGGAAUCUGCUGGCUCUUCGUCAGAUUGGGCAGAGGACGAUAAGCACUGCUUCCCGCAGGCAUUUUAAAAAUAAAGUUCCGGAGAAGCAAAAACUGUUCCAGGAGGAUGAUGAAAUUCCACUGUAUCUAAAGGGUGGGGUAGCUGAUGCCCUCCUGUAUAGAGCCACCAUGAUUCUUACAGUUGGUGGAACAGCAUAUGCCAUAUAUGAGCUGGCUGUGGCUUCAUUUCCCAAGAAGCAGGAGUGACUUCAGUCAUCCCAGCAAUCGCUUGGUUCAGUUUCAUUCAGCUCUCUAUGGACCAGUAAUCUGAUAAAUAACCGAGCUCUUCUUUGGGGAUCAAUAUUUAUUGACUUGUAGUAACUGCCACCAAUAAAGCAGUCUUUACCAUGCUUUGUCUGAUUUUAUCACUUUAUGCCAAUAAUUUCAACUUUUGGUCAGCCUUGUAAAUCUUAGGUAAGGAUCAAAGAAAUGAUUCUUUUGCCACUAAACUUGUGAAAGCAA